AGAGUUUACAAAGGUCUAGGAUGACAUCUGGUGUAUUGACUGUGGCCAGUCUUAAAGCUAGUUUUUGCUAUGUGGAACAUGCUGCUCUAAUUCAGAUUUAAAGAGUUUCUUCCUGUUAAUUCGAAGCUCACUGUGCCUCUUGUUUCCGAGGGAAGAAGGACUGAUUAAGUCAUCUAAAUGGAUGCAAUACUGAAUUACAGGUCAGAAGAUACUGAAGAUUACUACACAUUACUGGGAUGUGAUGAACUAUCUUCGGUUGAACAAAUCCUGGCAGAAUUUAAAGUCAGAGCUCUGGAAUGUCACCCAGACAAGCAUCCUGAAAACCCCAAAGCUGUGGAGACUUUUCAGAAACUGCAGAAGGCAAAGGAGAUUCUGACCAAUGAAGAGAGUCGAGCCCGCUAUGACCACUGGCGAAGGAGCCAGAUGUCGAUGCCAUUCCAGCAGUGGGAAGCUUUGAAUGACUCAGUGAAGACGUCAAUGCACUGGGUUGUCAGAGGUAAAAAAGACCUGAUGCUGGAAGAAUCUGACAAGACUCAUACCACCAAGAUGGAAAAUGAGGAAUGUAAUGAGCAAAGAGAAAGAAAGAAAGAGGAGCUGGCUUCAACCGCAGAGAAAACGGAGCAGAAAGAACCCAAGCCCCUAGAGAAGUCAGUCUCCCCGCAAAAUUCAGAUUCUUCAGGUUUUGCAGAUGUGAAUGGUUGGCACCUUCGUUUCCGCUGGUCCAAGGAUGCUCCCUCAGAACUCCUGAGGAAGUUCAGAAACUAUGAAAUAUGAAAUAUCUCUGCUUCAAAAAAUGAGGAAGAGCAAGACUGUCCCCUAUGCUGCCAACAUGCAGUCUUUGUUUAUGUCUUAAAAAUGUCAUGUUUAUGUCAUGUCUGUGAAUUGCUGAGUACUAAUUGAUUCCUCCAUCCUUGAAUCAGUUCUCAUAAUGCUUUUUAAAUAAGAAAAAUUCAGAAGAUGAAUUUCUUCCAAUAUUUGAAUAAAUUAAAGCUCUUAGAUACAGAGUAGAUUGUAUUAUAUGCUUUUUCCUAUUAAUACUACUUAUAGAAAUCCAUUAAAAAGCAAUCUCUGUACAGUGUAUUUAAAUAUUUCAUUGACAUACUGUGAUCUCUAUUAGUGAUGGAUGUACAAAAAAUGUUUUCUUACCCUUGACUUACAAUGAAAUGUGAAAUUACUUGUCUGAACCCCGUGGGGAGAAAUAAAUAAUUUUCCCAAAGUUCA